GGUGUACUGCGCAUGCGGGAAGAUGGCGGGCCGGGCGACUUGAGAUCCGCGGGUCUCCCUCCUCUUUUUCCGUCUGCGUCGGGAGCUCCCGGGCACGUGAGGCCGUGCCGCGUUUACUGGCGGGCGGGACGGCCUAGCCGGGCGGCGCCUCGGAGGAAGCCGCGGACCCCUUAGGUGCUGGGCCCUUGGAAAUCGGCGCGUGGGGGGCGGUGCUCGAGCUGAGCGCGAGAGGGCGGGAGAGCUCGUGGGGUGCGAGGGGAGCAGGACGCCCGGCCGGGCAGCAUGAGUCAGCAGCGGCCGGCGAGGAAGUUACCCAGUCUCCUCCUGGACCCGACGGAGGAGACGGUUCGCCGUCGGUGCCGAGACCCCAUCAACGUGGAGGGCCUGCUGUUGUUUAUUCAGGCAAAUCUGGCUUGCUGGGCUAGGCUCAGCUGAGGGCUGCCUUCGCCAUGAAUCCUUCUCCAUCAAAAAUAAGGAUUAAUUUAGAAGAUAAUGUACAAUAUGUGUCCAUGAGAAUGUAGGAAUGGGCUCCAGAGAGAAGACAUUUAUAUUAUGAAAUAUGUACCUUUGUUCCUGAAGUAACCGCCAGUGGUCUUUAAACUAAAUGUGACAUUGUGGAGGUUCUGAGUAAGGACAUUUCUGACUGAAGAAGCUCUAAAAGUGAAGAGACCUCGUUUUGAUGUAUCGCUGGUUUAUUUAACUCGAAAAUUUAUGGAUCUUGUCAGAUCUGCUCCCGGGGGUAUUCUUGACUUAAACAAGGUUGCAACGAAACUGGGAGUCCGAAAGCGGAGAGUGUAUGACAUCACCAAUGUCUUAGAUGGAAUCGACCUCGUUGAAAAGAAAUCCAAGAACCAUAUUAGAUGGAUAGGAUCUGAUCUUAGCAAUUUUGGAGCAGUUCCCCAACAAAAGAAGCUACAGGAGGAACUUUCUGACUUAUCAGCAAUGGAAGAUGCUUUGGAUGAGUUAAUUAAGGAUUGUGCUCAGCAGCUGUUUGAGUUAACAGAUGACAAAGAAAAUGAAAGACUAGCAUAUGUGACCUAUCAAGACAUUCAUAGCAUUCAGGCCUUCCAUGAACAGAUCGUCAUUGCAGUUAAAGCUCCAGCAGAAACCAGAUUGGAUGUUCCAGCUCCCAGAGAAGACUCUAUCACAGUGCACAUAAGGAGCACCAACGGACCUAUCGAUGUCUAUUUGUGUGAAGUGGAGCAGGGUCAGACCAGUAACAAAAGGUCUGAAGGUGUCGGGACCUCUUCAUCUGAGAGCACUCAUCCAGAAGGCCCUGAGGAAGAAGAAAAUCCUCAGCAAAGUGAAGAAUUGCUUGAAGUAAGCAACUGAUGGCAUUUGAGAAUUUAUGUAUCACUGAGUUUUUUGGGAAUAUCUUCGUGGAGAAUUACGCAUCAAAUUUGAUUCUCAGAGCAAUAAAUUAUCCAUGAAGUGCUCUCGUUCUCAGUAGCGGCAUCAUGGCCAGUAGUGUCUUUGAGGAGUUCACCACUUAGAUUACUGAGUAAUUGUGGUUUCCACAUUUGAAAACAACUCCUUUUAUAAUUAUUCACUGCUUUUUGUCAGUGAAAUAGACAUCUUGCCUCCUGAAGUAGCUUCAUCACAGAGUGUCAUGAAGACAGACAGUCAGGCUGAAAUGGACAGUUCUUUGUGGACUCUACCCUUCCCUUCAAGGAGUAUGUCAUAUAUCACAAAAGAAAUUGCCUUACACUGGUUCAUGUUUGCAGUUACUGUUGUACAUUGCAUAGAUGUACACACGAAUUUAAAUGUGAUGUCUUUGUAUAUAUCUGUAUAAUGUUGAGAUUACUUACGAAAUAUGUCUGAGUGACACUUUUCACCCUUGUACAGCCAAAAUAAUGUAUAUAUGGAAAGUGACAGACAAAUUCUCUAAUCUCUUUGGUACCUAUAACUUAUUAGAAUCCUCUGGAUGAGGGUUAGAAGAGACUUUUUCCAAACUUCUACAUGUAGAAGUAUCAUAAAUGUGCUACACAUUUAUGUUUGUGGAUUUAAUUAAAGUAUUUUAAUAUGGUUUUCAGUGCUAAAAUUGGAGUCAGAUACUUCUUGGUUUUAAGCUGUCUACCUAAUUGCUGUCUCCCAGCAGACUGGUGGCAUGCCCAGUGGCUUUGGGGGCAAGGAUAGAAAUGCCAUCAGGAAAUAGCUGAAUUCAUUGUGAAACAUGAAUUCAGUCAUGGUGAUAAUUGGAAACUCCUUUCAGGUUUUUGCAAGUAGAUUUUGUAAUGUUUGUGUAUGCAGCCUUGCUGUUGAGUCAGUCCAAGGGGUUUUACUUAGGACAAGUUGUACCUUGCCCUCUCUCCAGCUCUGCUCCCACAUUUUCACAUACCUAGCUGUUUCUACCUCAUUGGGUAAGUCAUUUACCACUCUGUGCCUCAGUUUACUCUGUAGUUUACCAUUAGACUGUGAGCUCCUUGAGGGACUUUGUCAUAAUCACUGUUACAUCCCAGUGCCUCACACCAUGCCUGGCCCUUAAGAAGUGCUCAAUAAAUGUCUGAACAAAUAAGUGAGUGGAGUGAGUGAAUUGUAAGAUCAGAAUAAUAAUAUUUGGUUUGUCUAUCGUACAAGAUUCCUGUAUCGUUUGAAUAUUGCUUUUAAAGAAAUAUUUGAAGCGACUUCAAAUUCAGACUGUGUUUAAAAAGAUUUAAAAUCGGAAUCCAAAAUCAAAGUAUUAAAAAAUAAUGCUGAGUGUUUAGGAUUCACAUACCUCUGAGCUCUGGUGGCUUUUGCCAGUCCUGUCCCUCUGCUGAGCACCAGCCCUUCCUGCAGCAGUCCUGCCGGUGUGUUUCUGUGCACCUGGGGAUGAAGUGUGCUCCUCCCCCAGCGGUUAGCCUCAAUGCUUUUCCUCCCUCUGUUUUAUUAUUUGAAAUUAGCCAAAGAAAAGCUGCAGGGGGCACUGCUGAUCAUCACUGGACUGGUGGGUCGUACUGUUUGACAGAAUAGGGAAUACAGGAGGAGGAGCAAGCCUAGGGUAAAACUUAGGUUUGGGACAUGCUUGAUGAAAGCAAGAGUUGAGCAGGUUGUUGUGUGUAUGUAGGUCAGGUGCUCAGCGGAAAAGUCUGAGCUGUGUAGUACGUCAGGCAGAUGUCAGUUUAGAUGCGAUAGUUUAAGCCACAAGAGUAGGAGAGGUCAUCUAAAGAGUACAGCAGGCCUAAGGGCAUCUAUAUUUAAGGAGAAAUACAGAAGAAGUCUCCUGAGAAGGAAUAAUGGGGCGGGUGGGGAGGGAGAAGGCAGUGUCCCAAAAACCAACAAAGGUUUUACCAAAGGUAAUACCAUCAUUUCUGAGCAGCAGUUCCUUAACUUGUGAAUGUGGCAAAUGUUCUCCUUUACAAAUUGUUCUGAAGGUAAAAUGAGAUCAUGUAAACGAAAAUCCUUUGUAAAUUACAGAUGUGUGUUAUAAAUGAAGUAUCUCUCGAGUCACUCCA